GGAAGUGAGGGAGGGAGGACUUUCGUACGCAGCCGCCUCCCAGCUGGAACCUCAUCUUUAGUGCUCGGCCGCGGGCGGCGUAACUCGGGGUUCCGCCUCGGAAUACCUCCCACUUCUCUUGUCUAAGAGGAGCAGUAGCAAGCUGAGCUCAGAGCGAAGCUGGCGAGCCAAGGAGAUAAAGAACCCUCGGUGGGGAUGCCCAGAGGGUGCAUGCUCCACGCCCCUCGAAACCGAUUCUCAUUGCUGCUGCUGCAAAGCAACCCGAAGUGCGCCACCUACCCGACUGAGGCUGCGCAAGCCCCGGGGUCUGGGCGGGGUGGUCCUCGUGCGCGCCGCGUCGCCGUGGAGACGAGGGCGGGCCCGCGCGAGACUGGCGUCUAGAGGCGCGCGAAGCGCUGAGGCGGGCGUGGACCGCGCGGGAGUUAAGAAGCAGGUCCCGGAUCGCCGUAUACCGCCGGGUUUUCUCCCAACGUCAGGCCCGAUGGCUCGGCUUCCCCAGUUAGAAGGGGAAGAUAAAAGACUUUGAUUCAUGAAGAAUCUGCUCACUGAGAAGUGUAUAUCAAGCCACAAUUUCCAUCAAAAAGUGAUUAAGCAGAGAAUGGAGAAGAAGGUUGAUUCCAGGUAUUUUAAGGAUGGUGCAGUUAAGAAACCUUAUUCUGCAAAGACACUGUCCAACAAGAAGUCUUCUGCAUCCUUUGGGAUCCGGAGGGAGUUACCUAGUACCAGUCAUCUAGUGCAGUAUCGUGGCACACAUACUUGUACCCGACAGGGCCGGUUAAGAGAACUGCGCAUCAGAUUUUACUAUGAGCAGCGAUUACUACGGAAGGUCUUCGAAGAAUGGAAAGAGGAGUGGUGGGUUUUCCAGCACGAGUGGAAACUCUGUGUUCGAGCUGACUGUCACUACAGGUAUUACCUGUACAACCUGAUGUUCCAGACGUGGAAGACCUAUGUGCGUCAGCAGCAGGAGAUGAGGAACAAGUACAUUAGAGCCGAGGUUCAUGAUGCAAAGCAAAAGAUGCGACAGGCCUGGAAGUCCUGGUUGAUCUACGUGGUUGUUCGUAGGACCAAACUUCAGAUGCAGACUACAGCUCUGGAGUUUAGGCAACGGAUUAUCUUACGGGUGUGGUGGAGCACGUGGAGGCAGCGACUAGGACAGGUCCGUGUGAGCCGUGCCCUCCAUGCCUCUGCUUUGAAGCACAGGGCCCUGAGCCUCCAGGUGCAGGCUUGGUCACAGUGGCGGGAACAGCUCCUGUAUGUCCAGAAGGAGAAACAAAAGGUUGUCUCUGCAGUGAAACAUCAUCAGCACUGGCAAAAACGGAGAUUUCUAAAGGCCUGGCUUGAAUACCUGCAAGUCCGCAGAGUGAAGAGACAGCAGAAUGAGAUGGCUGAGCGAUUCCAUCAUGUCACUGUGCUCCAGAUAUACUUCUGUGACUGGCAGCAGGCCUGGGAGCGGAGGGAGAGCUUGUACGCUCACCAUGCCCAGGUGGAGAAACUGGCCAGGAAGAUGGCCCUGCGGCGCGCCUUUACUCACUGGAAACACUACAUGCUGCUGUGUGCAGAAGAAGCUGCCCAGUUUGAGAUGGCAGAAGAGCACCACAGGCACAGCCAGCUGCUGCUGCACAGGUUCUGGAACCUCUGGCGGUCUCAGAUUGAGCAGAAAAAGGAAAGAGAGCUGCUCCCCUUACUGCAUGCUGCCUGGGACCACUACAGAAUAGCACUGCUGUGCAAAUGUAUCGAAUUGUGGCUACAGUAUACUCAGAAGAGGCGGUACAAGCAGCUGCUACAGGCCAGAGCGGAUGGUCAUUUCCAGCAGAGAGCCCUGCCUGCUGCCUUCCACACAUGGAACAGACUCUGGCGAUGGCGCCACCAGGAAAAUGUCCUCAGUGCAAGAGCAACACGUUUCCACAGGGAGACAUUAGAGAAGCAAGUAUUUUCUCUCUGGAGGCAGAAGAUGUUUCAGCAUCGAGAAAACCGCCUGGCAGAGAGAAUGGCCAUCCUUCACGCAGAGCGACAGCUUCUGUAUAGGUCUUGGUUCAUGUGGCACCAGCAGGCAGCAGCACGUCACCAGGAGCAGGAGUGGCAAACAGUGGCCUGUGCCCACCACCGCCACGGGCGGCUCAAGAAAGCUUUCUGCCUCUGGAGGGAAAGUGCCCAAGGGCUCAGAACAGAGAGGACGGGCAGGGUGCGGGCAGCAGAAUUCCACAUGGCCCAGCUCCUGCGUUGGGCCUGGAGCCAGUGGAGGGAGUGCCUGGCCCUGCGGGGAGCGGAGCGGCAGAAGCUGAUGCGAGCAGACCUGCACCACCAGCACAGCGUGCUGCACAGGGCGCUGCAGGCAUGGGUGACUUACCAGGGCAGGGUGCGAAGCAUCCUCCGGGAGGUGGCAGCCAGGGAGAGCCAGCACAACAGGCAGCUGCUGCGCGGGGCAUUACGUCGCUGGAAAGAGAACACCAUGGCCCGAGUGGAUGAAGCCAAAAAAACCUUUCAAGCAAGUACUCAUUACAGAAGGACCAUAUGUUCCAAGGUCCUGGUCCAGUGGCGGGAAGCUGUGUCAGUGCAGAUGUAUUACCGACAGCAGGAGGACUGUGCCAUCUGGGAGGCCCAGAAGGUGCUGGACAGGGGCUGUCUGCGGACCUGGUUUCAGCGCUGGUGGGACUGCAGCCGGAGGUCAGCCCAGCAGAGACUGCAGCUGGAGAGGGCAGUGCAACACCACCACCGGCAGCUGCUGCUGGAGGGGCUGGCCCGGUGGAAGACGCACCAUCUGCAGUGUGUCAGGAAGAGGCUCCUGCACAGGCAGAGCACCCAACUGCUGGCACAGAGACUCAGCCGGACCUGCUUCCGCCAGUGGAGACAACAGCUGGCAGCCAGGAGGCAGGAGCAGCGGGCGACAGUGCGGGCCCUGUGGUUCUGGGCCUUCUCGCUGCAGGCAAAGGUGUGGGCCACGUGGCUGGCCUUUGUACUGGAAAGGAGGAGAAAGAAGGCGCGGCUGCAGUGGGCGCUCCAGGCCUACCAGGGGCAGCUCCUCCAGGAGGGUGCCACGCGGCUCCUGCGCUUUGCAGCCAGCAUGAAGGCCUCCCGGCAGCAGCUGCAGGCCCAGCAGCAGGUCCAGGCGGCUCACAGUCUCCAUCGUGCCGUCCGCCGCUGUGCCACGCUCUGGAAACAGAAAGUGCUGGGCCGGGGCGGGAAGCCUCAGCCCCUGGCAGCCAUCGCACCCAGCAGGAAAGUGACGUUUGAGGGUCCCCUUCUCAACCGCAUUGCUGCUGGGGCUGGGGAUGGCACCCUUGAGACCAAGAGGCCACAGGCUUCUCGGCCUCUGGGAGCUCUGGGCCGCCUGGCUGCUGAGGAGCCCCACGCCCUGGAGCUCAACACUGCCCACUCAGCGAGGAAGCAGCCGCGACGCCCACACUUCCUGUUGGAGCCUGCGCAGAGCCAGAGGCCUCAGAAGCCACAGGAACAUGGCCUAGGCAUGGCUCAGCCAGCAGCCCCCUCCCUGACGCGGCCCUUCCUGGCAGAGGCCCCGACAGCACUGGUCCCACACAGCCCCCUGCCUGGGGCCCUGUCAAGCGCCCCUGGCCCGAAGCAGCCCCCGACGGCAAGCACAGGCCCGGAGCUGCUGCUGCUGCCUCUUUCCUCCUUCAUGCCCUGCGGGGCGGCUGCACCAGCCAGGGUGUCAGCACAGCGGGCUACUCCUAGGGAUAAGCCCCCGGUCCCCUCAUCCCUGGCCAGUGUCCCUGACCCCCAUCUACUCCUUCCUGGGGACUUCUCAGCCACCAGGGCUGGGCCUGGACUUUCAACUGCAGGCAGCCUGGACCUUGAGGCUGAACUUGAGGAGAUCCAGCAGCAACUACUGCACUACCAGACCACCAAGCAGAACCUCUGGUCCUGUCGGCGGCAAGCGAGCAGCCUGCGCAGGUGGCUGGAGCUGAACAGAGAGGAGCCGGGGCCUGAGGACCAGGAAGUAGAGCAGCAGGUGCAGAAAGAGCUGGAACAGGUGGAAAUGCAGAUCCAGCUGCUGGCAGAGGAGCUCCAGGCUCAGCGCCAGCCCAUUGGCGCCUGCGUUGCCCGCAUCCAGGCCCUGCGGCAGGCCCUGUGCUAGCGUGUUCGCACCAGGAACGCAGGUGCUGGGCUGUCGGGGAGGCCUCAGGCCACCUCCAGGAACAGAACACAGUUUUAAGUUUGAUUUUUUUUAUUUCAAAAUGCUUUGCAAUUAAAUGAAUUACUGUUCAGAA